CUCCUAUCGAGCCCUGGCUCUCCGGGCAGCUGGAGGGGUCGCGCUGCGCCUGUUGGGGCUGCACCUCGGACCAGGGCUUCUGCUGCAUCUGCAGCCAUGUCGGGCCGCUCAGUGCCACAUGCCCACCCGGCCACCGCCGAGUACGAAUUUGCCAACCCGAGCCGCCUGGGUGAGCAGCGCUUCGGAGAAGGCCUCCUGCCAGAAGAGAUCCUGACCCCCACACUCUACCAUGGCUACUAUGUCCGGCCUCGGGCCGCCCCAGCUGGGGAGGGCAGCAGGGCAGGGGCCUCCGAGCUUAGGCUCAGUGAGGGCAAGUUCCAGGCAUUUCUGGAUGUGAGCCACUUUACCCCAGACGAGGUGACUGUGAGGACUGUGGAUAACCUGCUGGAGGUGUCUGCCCGGCACCCCCAGCGCCUGGACCGCCACGGCUUCGUGUCCCGAGAGUUCUGCCGCACCUAUGUCCUGCCUGCUGAUGUCGACCCCUGGCGAGUCCGAGCUGCUCUCUCCCAUGAUGGCAUCUUAAACCUGGAAGCACCUCGGGGUGGCCGACAUUUGGACACAGAGGUCAAUGAGGUCUACAUCUCCCUGCUCCCUGCGCCUCCUGAUCCAGAGGAAGAGGAGGAGGCAGCCAUAGUUGAGCCCUGAUUGCCACAGACCCAGCACCCAGCAAAUCCCUCUCUACCUCCCAAGGUGAUAUGGGCAGCUGCCCACCACUCCAGAGGUAGCAGCAUCCUUGGGGGAAGGGAAAGGUGCAUGGUCCACAAUGUAUGGUUUGGUCCCAUGGGACAUGUCAUAGCCUUGGUUUAGUUUUGGGUGGAGCUGAAUAAACCCAAAUCUCAGGGC